CUGCAGCCCUGGCUGCUGCAGGGAAAGGCACUGCCUUUCUUCUCCAGGUGUCUUUUGUUCUUCUUCCGCCCUGGCCCCUUGCUGCCAUGCAGGACUCUGCUGGGAGUGACGUGGGUCUCUUUCCCUGAGAGAGCUGAAGAUCUGCAAGGAGACCUUCUCCCUGCCUUUUGCUUCGCAUUUUGAAGGGAGGGAGGAGACUAGCCAGAACCACUGACCAGGGGAAGCACUCUUAUCCUCUUAGAAAGGACCUUAGGAAUCAUCUAUCCCCUCCACCCCAUCCCUGCCUUGCCACGAGGAUUAAUUGCUCUCUAAGUGCCUUGGCCAAUGUUGACUUUCAGCCUAAGCUUGACCUCUCAAGCAAGUUGUUUCCUUCCUAACAAUAGUAUUUCAAGUGAAUUCAUUAAAACUUCUUAGUUGCAAGUAAUAGAAACUAACUUAAAUUAACUCAAGCAAAAAACAAACAAAACAAAACAAAAACAAAAAACAAACCAAGGAGUGGUCAGAAAUCCACUCCUCGGGGGAAUUUGAUCUCUUGCUUUUCUUGGCAACUUGAGGACCCUUUUCCUAGGAAAGGGGGACUUUCCCUGUCCCCCUCUGACUUCCAGCACAUAAUCAGUGAUUGUGACUCCAGUCCAGGUCCACUCAAUACCCACUUAUCAUAUGUGCUGCAUUACAACCAACAGAUGAAGAGGCACAGAUGGAUGCCUCUUUCAUCUGGUGAACUGAUAGAAGUGCUGUGAUGAACCUCCACAGUAGAAGAAAAGAAAAGGAUGAAAGACACAUGUUGCUAAUUGGCCUUAAACCUCCUCUGAUGGGAACAGGAGGCAGAAGCUGGUCAUGAGGGAAAACCAGACUCUGUCCAUGAGAGGAGCAACAAUGCAGAGCCGUGGCCAGUACAGCUGCACUGGGCAGGUGAUGUAUAUUCCACAGACAUUCACACAAACUUCAGAGACUGCCAUGGUUCAAGUCCAAGGCAGCCAAAGGAGACUCUGGAGAUGGUGUGGAUCCGAGGAAGUGGUUGCGGUCCUUCAGGAGUCCAUCAGCCUCCCCCUGGAAAUACCACCAGAUGAAGAGGUUGAGAACAUCAUCUGGUCCUCUCACAAAAGUCUUGCCACUGUGGUGCCAGGGAAAGAGGGACAUCCAGCUACCAUCAUGGUGACCAAUCCACACUACCAGGGCCAAGUGAGCUUCCUGGACCCCAGCUAUUCCCUGCAUAUCAGCAAUCUGAGCUGGGAGGAUUCAGGGCUUUACCAAGCUCAAGUCAACCUGAGAACAUCCCAGAUCUCUACCAUGCAGCAGUACAAUAUAUGUGUCUACCGAUGGCUGUCAGAGCCCCAGAUCACUGUGAACUUUGAGAGUUCUGGGGAAGGUGCCUGCAGUAUGUCCCUGGUGUGCUCUGUGGAGAAGGCAGGCAUGGAUAUGACCUACAGCUGGCUCUCCCGGGGGGAUAGCACUUAUACAUUCCAUGAAGGCCCUGUCCUCAGCACAUCCUGGAGGCCGGGGGACAGUGCCCUCUCCUACACCUGCAGAGCCAACAACCCCAUCAGCAACGUCAGUUCUUGCCCCAUCCCUGAUGGGCCCUUCUAUGCAGAUCCUAACUAUGCUUCUGAGAAGCCUUCAACAGCCUUCUGCCUCCUGGCCAAGGGAUUGCUCAUCUUCUUGCUCUUGGUAAUUCUGGCCAUGGGACUCUGGGUCAUCCGAGUCCAGAAAAGACACAAAAUGCCAAGGAUGAAGAAACUCAUGAGAAACAGAAUGAAAUUGAGGAAGGAGGCAAAGCCUGGCUCCAGCCCUGCCUGACUGCUCCUUGGGAACCCCAGUCCUGAGCUUGGUUUCUUCCCAGCACCCAGAGAAUCCUUCCUCAGCUCUCUUCUUUCCAGGGGAAGGAGGUGCUCAGGGGUGGGUAUCCAGAGAGCCAUACUUCUGAGGGAAGACUGGCUGGCAAUAAAGUCAAAUUAAGUGACCACAA